UUUGGUUACUGUAGCUCUGUAGUACAAUUUGAAGUCAGGUAAUUUGAUUCCCCCAGUUUUGUUCUUUUUGCCGAGGAUAGCUUUGUCUGUUUGGGGUCUUUUAGUGAUUCCAUAUAAGUUUUAGGACUGUUUUUUUUUUCUAAUUCUGUGAAGAAUGUCAUUGGUGUUUUGAUAGGGAUUGUAUUGAAUCUGUAGAUUGCUUUGAGUAGUAUGGACAUUUUAGCAAUAUUGAUUCUUCCAACCCAUGAACAUGGAAUAUCUUUCUACUUUUUGGUAUCUUCUUCAAUUUCCCUCAUCAGUGUUUUAUAGUUUUCAUUAUAGAGGUCUUUCACUUCUUUGGUUAAUUCUUAGAUAUUUAAUUUUAUGUGUGGCUAUUGUAAAUGGGGUUAUAUUUUUAAAUUUCUUUUUCACAUUGUUCACUGUUGGCAUAUAGAAAUGCUAAUGAUUUUUGCAUGUUGAUUUUGUAUUCUGCAACUUUACUGAAUUUAUCUGUUUUAAUAGUUUUCUUGUGGAGUCAUUAGGUUUUUCCAAAUAUAGGAUUACAUUAUCAGCAAACAAGGAUAAUUUGACUUCUUCCUUUCCAAUUUAGAUGCCCUUUAUAUUUUUCUCUUGACUGAUUGUUCUAGCUAGGACUUACAGUAAUAUAUUGAAUAACAGUGGAGAGAGUGGGCAUCCUUGUAGUGUUACCGAUUUUAGAGAAAAGUCUUUCUGUUUUUCCCCUUUAGUAUGAUACUAGCUGUAGGCCUGUGGCGUAUGAUUUUUAUUAUGUUGAUGUAUGUUCCUUCUAUCCCCAGUUUUUUGACAGUUUUUAUACUGAAGAGAUGUUGAAUUUUAUGAAAUGCUUUUUCAGCAUCAAUUGACAUGAUCAUAUGGUUUUCUCCUUCAUUCUAUUUAUAAGAUGUAUCAUGUCAACUGAUUUGCAAAUGUUGAACCAUCCUUGCCUCCCAGGGAUAUUUUCCAACUUGUCAUGAUGAAUGAACUUUCUAAUGUAUUGUUGCAUUCAGUUUGCUAGUAUUUUGUUGAGGAUUUUUGCAUCAGUAUUCAUCAGAAAUAUUAGCCUGUAGUUUUUUUUUUAAUUUAUGUGUCUUUUUUUCUUUUCUUUUUUUUUUUUGUAUCAGGGUAAUACUGGCUUCCUAGAAUGACUUUGGAAGUAUUCCCUCCUCUUAUAUAUUUUUUGGAAUAGUUUGACUAGGAUGGGUAUUAGUUCUUCCUUAAAUGUUUGACAGAAUUCAGCAGUGAAGCCAUAGGGUCCUGGACUUGACUUUACGGGAAGACAUUUUAUUAUGGCUUCAAUCUUGUUACUUGCUAUCUGUUCAGAUUUUUGAUUUCUUCCUGUUUCAAUCUUGGUAGGUUGUAUAUAUCUAGGAAUUUGUCCAUUUCUUCUACAUUUUCCAACUUAUUGGCAUAUAGUUGCUUAUCGUGGCUACUAAUGAUCCUUUGAAUUUCUGCAGUAUUGGUUGUAAUGUCUUCUUUUUCAUUUCUGAUUUUAUUUGUUUGGACCUUCUCUCUUUUACUCUUAGUCUGGCUAAGGGUUUAUCAAUUUUGUUUAACUUUUCAAAUAAAGCAACCUUCUGUUUUAUUGAUUUUUUUUGUAUUUUUUAUUUCAAUUUCAUUUAUUUCUGCUCUGAUCUUUAUUAUUUCUUUUAUUCUAGGUUUAAGUUUGGUUUGUUCUUACUAUUCUAGUUCUUGUUAGGUUUUUUGAGAUUUUUCCUUUUUUUUUUUUUUUUUCGAUGUAGGCACUUAUAAACUUCCCCCUGAGUACUGCUUUGGCUGAAUCCCAAAGGUUUUGGUAUGCUUUGUUUCCAUUAUCUUUGUUUCAAGAAAUUUUCCAAUUUCCUUCUCACUUUCUUCAUUGACCCACUGGUCUUUCAGGAGCAUAUUGUUUAAUUUCCAUGUAUUUGCAUAAUUUCCAAAAUUCCCUCUUGUUAUCAAUUUCUAGUUUUAUUCCAUUUUGGUUAGAGAAGAUGCCUGAUAUUAUAUUACUUCAAUUUUUGGAAUGGUUUAAUGCUUGUUUUAUGAUGUAGCAUAUGGUCUUUCCUUGAGAAUGAUCCACAUGCUGAGGAAAAGAAUGGUAUUCUGCAGCUCUUGGUUAUAAUGUUCUGUAAAUCUUUAUUAGAGUCAUUUGGCCUAUAGUGCAGAUUAAAUCUGAUAUUUCUUGGUUGAUUUUCUGUCUGGAAGAUGUGCCCAGUGCUUAAAGUGGGGUGUUGAAGUCUUCAGCUAUUAUUGUAUUGUGGCCUAUUCUCUCUCAAUAGCUCUAAUAAUGUUUUCUUUCUUUAUAUGGGUGCUCCAGUGUUGGUUGCAUAUAUAUAUUUAAAAUUGUUAUAUCCUCUUGUUGAAUGGACUCCUUUAUCAUUAUAUAGUGACCUUCUUUGUCCCUUACAGUUUUUGUCUUGAAAUCUAUUUUGUCUGAUAUAAAUAUAGCAACUCCUGCUCUUUUUUGGUUUUUAUUGGCCUGGCAUAUCUCUUUCCAUUAUUUUAUUUUCAGUCUAUAUGUCUCUUUAUAGGUGAAGUGUGUUUCUUGUAGGCAACAGAUCAAUGGGUCUUAUUUUUUCAUCUAUUUAGCCAUUUUAUGUCUUUUGAUUAGAUAGUUUAGUUCAUUUACAUUUAAUGUUAUUAUUGAUAAGUAAGGACUUAUACUCCUGCCAUUUUGUUAUUUGUUUUCUGGUUGUUUUGUUGUCGUAUCUUCCUUGUUUCUUUUCUUCCUGUAUUCCUCUAGCAAAGGUGAUUUUCUCUGAUUAUAUGAUUUAGUUUCUUGCUUUUUAUUCUCUAUGUAUUCACCAUAUGUUUUUGGGUUUGAGGUUACCAUGAGGUUGCAAAUACUAUCUUAUAAACCAUUAUUUUAACCUGAUAACAUCUUAACAGUAUUUCCACGAACAAAUAAGCAAAAAGAAAUCCAACAAAAACUCUCUGCCUUAACUUUGUACCCCAACUUUUUAAACUUUUUUUGUUUCUAUUUAUAUCUUUGUACUGACUAUGUCUUGAAAAGUUUUUAUAGUUAUUAGUUUUGAUUGUGUCAUUGUUUAGUCUUUUUACUUAGGACAAAAGUAGUUUGCACACCACAGUAACAGUGUUAUAAUAUUCUGUGUUUUUCUGUGUACUUACUAUUACCAGUGAGUUUUGUACCUUCAGAUGAUUAUGUAUUACUCAUUAAUGUCCUUUUCUUUCUGAAUGAAGUACCUCCUUAAGCAUUUUUUGUAGGACAGGUCUGGUAUUGCUGAAAUCCCUCAGUUUUUGUUUGUCUGGGAAAGUGUUUAUUUUUCCUUCAUGUUAGAAGGGUAUUUUUGCCAGAUAUACUAUUCAAGGGGAAAUUUUUUUUUACUUCAGCACAGUACAUGACACGCUACUCUCUCCUGGCUUGUAAGUUUUCCACUGCUGCCAGUGUAUUGGAGCUCAAUUGUAUGUUUUUUGUUUCUUUUCUCUUGCUGGUUUUAGGAUUCUUUCCUUAUCCUUAACAUUUGAGAUUUUGAUUAUUAAAUGCCUUGAGGUAGUCUUCUUUGAAUUAAAUCUGCUUGGUGUUCUAUAACCUUUUUGUAUUUGGAUAUCGGUAUCUUUUUCUAGGUUUGGGAAGUUCUCUGUUAUUUCUUUGUAAAAACUUUCUACCUUUAUCUCUUUUUCUACCUCUUCUUUAAGGCCAAUAACUCUUAUAUUUGCCCUUUUGAGGCAAUUUUCUAGAUCCUGUAGGUUUGCUUCAUUGUUUUUUAUUCUUUUUUGUUUUGUCUCUUCUGACUGUGUGUUUUCAAAUAGCCUGUCUUCAAGAUCACUAAUUCUUUCUUUUGUUUGUUCAAUUCUGCUAUUAAAAGACUGUGAUUCACUCUUCAAUAUGCUAAUUGCAUUUUUCAACUCCAGAAUUCCUGCUUGAGUCUUCUUAAUUAUUUCAAGUUCACUUGGUGUUCUAUCACUCUGUGGCUCUGCUGGUACCUGAAGCCAGUAAGUCUCAAAGGUUCACCCAAAGUCCUCGAUGUAGUACCUGGGUGUCACUGCUGGUUAUUCAGCGCUUUUCAGUUAGUAGGUGGCAAAUACUGCCAGGACUGGGUUCCUUUCUUCAAGGCAGUGGGUUCCCUUCUGGCCCAGGGGAUGUCUGGAAAUGUCUUUUGGGAGCUAGGACCUGGAAUGGAGGCCUCACAACUCUAACUGGCACCCUAUCCUGUGUGGUUGUGCUCAUAUCCUAGAUGUAAGACAAAGUCUUCCACACGUUUCCCUCUCCCCUCCUCAAGCACAAGGAAGGAGUCUCUUUGGAGCCACCAGCUAUGCAGCCUGAGGUUAGGGGAGGGGUGAUGCCAGAACUCCCUUGGCCAUCCUAGCUGGUGUCUCAGUAUAUUGUGUGUACCUCCUAGUCCACUGUCUCUAGCACUUGCCUAAGAGUUGCAGUCCUUAUGGCCUAGCCUGCCUUUCAAGUUUUCUUGGAGGCUCAGAGUGCUGUAGCCUCAGUAUCAAGGUUUAUAGGCUGCCCUCCCUAUUCUCAUUUUAUAGGAAAAAAAAAAAAAGAGACAGGAAGCGGAAAGAUUUUUAAGAAAUACACAAGGGAUGAUGUGAUUCCCACUAUGCCAUUUUGCAUACCAGGAGACCCUGGACCCUUGACUCUACAGCCAAUUUAUAUAUUGCUUGGAUUACUGCAGUUUAUUGCCUUCUCUGUGUCUUCUUGAUUUCCGUCUAACCCUCUCAUAAUCUAGUUUCCAAUUUUUCUAAAAGGUGCAUUUUCUGGGAUUCUUCACAACUUCAGAGUAAAAUUCAUACUCUUCAGCUAGGCGCACAACAACCUGAAUAUGAUAAAGGAAGACCUAGGUCUAGAAAAAUAGCAGAAAGUGGAAGAGGGAAACGAUAUUCAUACAAAUUACCUCAAGAAUACAACAUAGAGACUGUAGUGGUUGCAGACCCAGCAAUGGUUUCCUAUCAUGGAGCAGAUGCAGCCAGGAGAUUCAUUCUAACCAUCUUAAAUAUGGUAUUUAACCUUUUCCAACACAAGAGUCUGAGUGUGCAGGUCAAUCUUCGUGUGAUAAAGCUUAUUCUGCUCCAUGAAACUCCACCAGAACUAUAUAUUGGGCAUCAUGGAGAAAAAAUGCUAGAGAGUUUUUGUAAGUGGCAACAUGAAGAAUUUGGCAAAAAGAAUGAUAUACAUUUAGAGAUGUCAACAAACUGGGGGGAAGACAUGACUUCAGUGGAUGCAGCUAUACUUAUAACAAGGAAAGAUUUCUGUGUGCACAAAGAUGAACCAUGUGAUACUGUUGGUAUAGCUUACUUGAGUGGAAUGUGUAGUGAAAAGAGAAAAUGUAUUAUUGCUGAAGACAAUGGCUUGAAUCUUGCUUUUACAAUUGCUCAUGAAAUGGGUCACAACAUGGGCAUUAACCAUGACAAUGACCACCCAUCGUGUGCUGAUGGUCUUCAUAUCAUGUCUGGUGAAUGGAUUAAAGGACAGAAUCUUGGUGACGUUUCAUGGUCUCGAUGUAGCAAGGAAGAUUUGGAAAGAUUUCUCAGGUCAAAGGCCAGUAACUGCUUGCUACAAACAAAUCCGCAGAGUGUCAAUUCUGUGAUGGUUCCCUCCAAGCUGCCAGGGAUGACAUACACUGCUGAUGAACAAUGCCAGAUCCUUUUUGGGCCAUUGGCUUCUUUUUGUCAGGAGAUGCAGGUAAAGAUCCAGCAUGUUAUUUGCACAGGAUUAUGGUGCAAGGUAGAAGGUGAGAAAGAAUGCAGAACCAAGCUAGACCCACCAAUGGAUGGAACUGACUGUGACCUUGGUAAGUGGUGUAAGGCUGGAGAAUGUACCAGCAGGACCUCAGCACCUGAACAUCUGGCCGGAGAGUGGAGCCUGUGGAGUCCUUGUAGCCGAACCUGCAGUGCUGGGAUCAGCAGUCGAGAGCGCAAAUGUCCUGGGCUAGAUUCUGAAGCAAGGGAUUGUAAUGGUCCCAGAAAACAAUACAGAAUAUGUGAGAAUCCACCUUGUCCUGCAGGUUUGCCUGGAUUCAGAGACUGGCAAUGUCAGGCUUAUAGUGUUAGAACUUCCUCCCCAAAGCAUAUACUUCAGUGGCAAGCUGUCCUGGAUGAAGAAAAACCAUGUGCCUUGUUUUGCUCUCCUGUUGGAAAAGAACAGCCUAUUCUUCUAUCAGAAAAAGUGAUGGAUGGAACUUCUUGUGGCUAUCAGGGAUUAGAUAUCUGUGCAAAUGGCAGGUGCCAGAAAGUUGGCUGUGAUGGUUUAUUAGGGUCUCUUGCAAGAGAAGAUCAUUGUGGUGUAUGCAAUGGCAAUGGAAAAUCAUGCAAGAUCAUUAAAGGGGAUUUUAAUCACACCAGAGGAGCAGGUUAUGUAGAAGUGCUGGUGAUACCUGCUGGAGCAAGAAGAAUCAAAGUUGUGGAGGAAAAGCCGGCACAUAGCUAUUUAGGUAACCUGUGUUACAGACACAGAGAAGAUCCAACUCUCCGAGAUGCUGGCAAACAGUCUAUUAAUAGUGACUGGAAGAUUGAACACUCUGGAGCCUUCAAUUUGGCUGGAACUACCGUUCAUUAUGUAAGACGAGGCCUCUGGGAGAAGAUCUCUGCCAAAGGUCCUACUACAGCACCUUUACAUCUUCUGGUGCUCCUGUUUCAGGAUCAGAAUUAUGGUCUUCACUAUGAAUACACUAUCCCAUCAGACCCUCUUCCAGAAAACCAGAGCUCUAAAGCACCUGAGCCCCUCUUCAUGUGGACACACACAAGCUGGGAAGAUUGCGAUGCCACUUGUGGAGGAGGAGAAAGGAAGACAACAGUGUCCUGCACAAAAAUCAUGAGCAAAAAUAUCAGCAUUGUGGACAAUGAGAAAUGCAAAUACUUAACCAAGCCAGAGCCACAGAUUCGAAAGUGCAAUGAGCAACCAUGUCAAACAAGGUGGAUGAUGACAGAAUGGACCCCUUGUUCACGAACUUGUGGAAAAGGAAUGCAGAGCAGACAAGUGGCCUGUACCCAACAACUGAGCAAUGGAACACUGAUUAGAGCCCGAGAGAGGGACUGCAUUGGGCCCAAGCCCGCCUCUGCCCAGCGCUGUGAGGGCCAGGACUGCAUGACCGUGUGGGAGGCGGGAGUGUGGUCUGAGUGUUCAGUCAAGUGUGGCAAAGGCAUACGUCAUCGGACCGUUAGAUGUACCAACCCAAGAAAGAAGUGUGUCCUCUCUACCAGACCCAGGGAGGCUGAAGACUGUGAGGAUUAUUCAAAAUGCUAUGUGUGGCGAAUGGGUGACUGGUCUAAGUGCUCAAUUACCUGUGGCAAAGGAAUGCAGUCCCGUGUAAUCCAAUGCAUGCAUAAGAUCACAGGAAGACAUGGAAAUGAAUGUUUUUCCUCAGAAAAACCUGCAGCAUACAGGCCAUGCCAUCUUCAACCCUGCAAUGAGAAAAUUAAUGUAAAUACCAUAACAUCACCCAGACUGGCUGCUCUGACUUUCAAGUGCCUGGGAGAUCAGUGGCCAGUGUACUGCCGAGUGAUACGUGAAAAGAACCUAUGUCAGGACAUGCGGUGGUAUCAGCGCUGCUGUGAAACAUGCAGGGACUUCUAUGCCCAAAAGCUGCAGCAGAAGAGUUGACCUCUAGCAGGCUGGCUGGAUCACAGCUCUUGGCAAUUACAUUAUUUAUAAACACACACACUAGCAUGUUUUUCAGACCAAAUAUUAUCAGAUUACAUAUAAUUUAAUCAAAUUAAUUUAUUUUUUUGCCUGCCAAACAUCCAAUGUGGUGCUUGUUUUGGUUACACAAACAUUUUGAUUUAUACUAUAUGGCUUCAUAAAUAAUUUUAUAUGAAUGAAUUAGUUGGAUCCAGUAAUAUAAUAAAAAGAAAAAGGAAAAAAAUAGAUCAUUAUACUUAAAACAAGUUUUCGUUGUUUGUUAGGGCUAUCUCUAAGGUGCUACUCUCUCCCCACCAAUAACAUUGAAUUAUCCAGAAUGUAUACUGACUUAGCAUAAUAGUUUAGGUGUAUAUGAAGAGAAACUAUUUUUGUUUUUUGGUGUCCUGCUGCAGAAUUAGCCCAUUUUCUGUCACCUGCAGGAGAUGUGUAAACAUAAUGAACCUCAUGCUGUUGAACAGGUUUUUAGAGAAUGUAUUAUGAAUUUGGUUCAGAUUUAUAGACAUCCAUAGGAAAAAUUCUGCUGUAAUUAUAACCUUAUUUUGAUAUGGAAAAGAAAAGUCAAAAUAGAGACUUUGAUCAUGUUCAUGAACAUGUACUUGAACACAAGUAUUGUAACAAUGAAACACUGUAAUGAUUUACACUGAAUCACAAUUGCACUGUUGAUAUAGUGUAGAGAAAUCGUUAGAAAUGGUGACAUCUUACAAAAAAUGUGUAUUAUUUUAACAUGUUAUCACUAGAUUUUAGCUUUUUUUAAAUAUUUUUAACAAAGAAAACAUUGAUCCACCCAUUUCCCUGUAUCUUUUUAGCAGAUUUAUUAAAGAGUAUAGUACUUAGCCUCACGAAUCAUAAUUAGAAAAUUUACUAGUAUUUCUCAGCCUUUUCCCUAGGAACAAGGAAAAACAGAAAGCAUAUAAUACGGUGGUCGUUUCAUUGUGUUUUUCUUCCUUUUAAAAAUUAAAAAGUUUUACAAUUAUGUGAAACGUUCAAAAGCCAGCUUAAAAUUUUUCUUGUGAGAAAAUAUUAUACAUGAUUCACAUGAUUUCUUAGAUUUUUCAAUAAAAUAUGUAAAACUUCCCACUGAGAGACAAUUCUUCAUAGACUUGUCACAUAUCCACAUGUCUGAUGAACAAAGGUACUGUCUACUUUUGUUCUGGAGUAUCUUCUAGAGGAUGUUUAUAGAGUGAACUGCCUUGGAAGAUAGUAUGUCUCUUGGGAGCAAAGGGCAAACAUACUUCUCAUUAUAAAAGUUUCAGGUUCCCUAAAAUUGGGGUUUCUUUACUAUAAGACAAUCCAAUGUAUGUUCUGAGGUCACCUGGCUCUCUUCAUGUCACCCUUUGGGAAAUGGGGCUCAACGAGCCAGUACAGGAAAAGCUGAUUCCCUGGCUACUACUAUCGCUGUGAGUAAUAAAGUCCUUUGUGUCUAAUG